GCAGUCGCGGGCCUCUCCCGGAGAAGAUGGCGGAUCGCGCGGAGAUGUUUUCUCUCUCCACCUUCCACUCGCUGUCGCCGCCGGGCUGCAGGCCUCCCCAGGACAUAAGCCUGGAAGAAUUUGACGACGAAGAUCUGUCUGAGAUCACUGAUGACUGUGGCCUGGGCCUCAGCUACGACUCAGACCACUGUGAGAAGGACAGCCUCUCCCUGGGGCGCUCGGAGCAGCCGCACCCCAUCUGCUCCUUCCAGGAUGACUUCCAGGAGUUUGAGAUGAUCGAUGACAAUGAAGAGGAGGACGAUGAGGACGAGGAAGAGGAGGAGGAGGAGGAGGAGGGAGAUGGGGAAGGCCAGGAGGGAGGAGACCCUGGCUCAGAGGCACCUGCCCCCGGGCCCCUUAUCCCCUCCCCUUCCGUGGAGGAGCCCCACAAGCACCGGCCCACCACCCUCCGUCUGACCACACUGGGGGCCCAGGACUCCCUAAACAACAACGGAGGCUUUGACCUGGUGCGUCCGGCCUCCUGGCAGGAGACAGCGCUAUGCUCACCCGCCCCGGAGGCCCUCAGAGCAGAGCUCCCGGGCCCCCUCCCUGCCACGGACACCGGGCCCGGCGGGGCGCAGUCGCCAGUGCGCCCGGGUUGCGACUGCGAAGGGAACCGGCCUGCGGAACCCCCUGCGCCAGGGGGGACUUCGCCCUCCUCAGAUCCCGGCAUCGAGGCUGACCUGAGAAGCCGCUCGAGCGGCGGCCGCGGGGGACGUCGCAGCAGCCAGGAGCUGUCCUCGCCCGGCUCCGACUCGGAGGACGCGGGCGGCGCGCGCCUGGGGCGCAUGAUCUCGUCCAUCUCGGAGACGGAGCUGGAGCUGAGCAGCGAUGGCGGAAGCAGCAGCAGCGGCCGCUCCUCGCACCUCACCAACUCCAUCGAGGAGGCCUCGUCGCCCGCCUCGGAGCCGGAGCCCCCGCGCGAACCCCCGCGCCGCCCCGCCUUCCUGCCCGUGGGCCCCGACGACACCAACAGCGAGUACGAGUCGGGGUCGGAGUCGGAGCCGGACCUCAGCGAGGACGCGGACUCGCCCUGGCUGCUCAGCAACCUGGUGAGCCGCAUGAUCUCCGAGGGCUCCUCGCCCAUCCGCUGCCCCGGCCAGUGCCUGUCUCCUGCGCCGCGCCCGCCCGGGGAGCCCGUGUCGCCGGCCGGCGGGGCCGCCCAGGACUCCCAGGACCCCGAGGCGGCCGCGGGGCCCGGCGGCGUGGAGCUGGUGGACAUGGAGACGCUGUGCGCGCCGCCGCCGCCCGCGCCCGCCGCGCCUCGACCCGGCCCCGCGCAGCCCGGGCCCUGCCUAUUCCUCAGCAACCCCACGCGUGACACCAUCACGCCGCUGUGGGCCGCGCCCGGCCGCGCCGCCCGCCCGGGACGAGCCUGCUCCGCCGCCUGCUCCGAGGAGGAGGACGAAGAGGACGACGAGGAAGAGGAGGAUGCCGAGGACAGUGCGGGGUCCCCCGGGGGCAGGGGCACGGGCCCCUCGGCGCCGCGGGACGCGUCGCUGGUGUACGACGCGGUCAAGUACACGCUGGUGGUGGAUGAGCACACGCAGCUGGAGCUGGUGAGCCUGCGGCGCUGUGCUGGGCUGGGCCACGACAGCGAAGAGGACAGCGGCGGGGAGGCCAGCGAGGAGGAGGCGGGCGCGGCGCUGCUAGGCGGCGGUCAGGUCUCGGGGGACACCUCGCCGGACAGCCCUGACCUCACUUUCUCCAAGAAGUUCCUCAAUGUCUUCGUCAACAGCACAUCUCGGUCCUCCAGCACCGAGUCCUUUGGCCUUUUCUCCUGUCUGGUCAACGGCGAGGAGCGAGAGCAGACUCACCGGGCUGUGUUCAGGUUCAUCCCGCGGCAUCCAGACGAGCUGGAGCUGGAUGUGGAUGACCCUGUGUUGGUGGAGGCCGAGGAGGACGACUUCUGGUUCCGUGGCUUCAACAUGCGCACGGGGGAGCGCGGUGUGUUUCCUGCCUUCUACGCCCAUGCGGUGCCCGGCCCUGCCAAGGACCUGCUGGGGAGUAAGCGGAGCCCCUGCUGGGUGGAGCGCUUUGACGUGCAGUUCCUGGGCUCCGUGGAGGUGCCCUGCCACCAGGGCAACGGCAUCCUGUGUGCAGCCAUGCAGAAGAUUGCCACUGCCCGGAAACUGACCGUCCACCUGCGCCCUCCUGCCUCCUGUGACCUCGAGAUCUCUCUUCGGGGGGUCAAGCUGAGUCUGAGCGGAGGAGGGCCCGAGUUCCAGCGCUGCAGCCAUUUCUUCCAGAUGAAGAACAUCUCCUUCUGCGGCUGCCAUCCCCGCAACAGCUGCUAUUUCGGCUUCAUCACCAAACACCCCCUGCUGAGCCGCUUCGCCUGCCACGUCUUUGUCUCCCAGGAGUCCAUGAGGCCGGUGGCGCAGAGUGUGGGCCGCGCCUUCCUGGAGUACUACCAAGAGCACCUGGCGUACGCCUGCCCCACGGAGGACAUCUACCUGGAGUAGCCUGCCCACCGCUCUGUCUCCUGGCCGUCUGCUCCAGGCGCAGCUGGGGCUGAGGAUGUCUCAAGAGGCCACCAUGGCUUUGGCAAGGACUGGAUUGGGGGGACAUGGGACCUUACGCUUGUGGGGGUCUGCGGGCUGGGAACUCUCGUCCUCGGUCCCCAGGGCGCAGCUGUUGGGGCUGCGGGGGAGUGGAGCCCCCGUGCCCCUGCUUUUCCUCAGAUCCGUUCUUUCUCUGUGUUGUCCUCCUCCUUCCCUUCCCAGUCUCCCUUUUCUCUCUCCUGGUGUCUCUGCCCCUCUCUGUGCCUGCAAACCUUAUCCUCUAUUCUUCACUUUGGGGUCAGAACUUCGGGGGUGUGGAGGAGGUGCGGCUCUAGGGACAGGUAAUGUCGGCUUCCAAGUGAUGCCCUCCUGCCACUCCCCUGCGAUUUAUAAGGGAAUUUUAAUUUUUAUAGUGAAUCUCAAGGGAUCAUCCCAUCCUUGACCACAGGGACAAGAGGGGCCCCCUCGCCCCAGCCCCACCCCACAUGGAGCUCAGGGGGAAGCAGGGAGGGGUUCCCAAAAGAGCCCUGCGGAGGCUAGGAGUGGUUCUUGAUGCUCACCUGAAGCCCCUAGACGCUGCUAGGAGGGGGGGCCCUCCUGGGCCCCCAAUACCCCUCCGCUUGCCGCUGCUAGCGCACCCCUGCAGUCCAGCGUGCAUCCACCCCACGCACGCCCCGUGCUGUGUUCCUGGGCCCUGCCCAUGGCCUCAAUAAACUCUCUGCUUGGUGUGACAUUGGCUGUUUCUAGAGGGUGCUAAGACAUGGGGCCAGGUGCCCAGGGGCUGCCCAUUGUGGUAGGGACAGAGUCCCCAGUGGCGGGAGUGUUGUGGCAAUCUCACCCUUUUAGCUCUUUCCGAAAUUGUGCCGGGGGUCCCUGCGGUGCUGCUCUGGGGCCUUAUCUGAGGUGCCGUAUCUAGAAGCACCCUUGGGAAUUCUCCCUAGAUACACUCGAUUGGCCACAGAGGAAUCCGAGGCUGUGCAAUGGGGUGUCCUUUCCACGUGCACGGACUGGGGGCCAGCACGGCUCAGGUCAGUGUGUAGUGGGGGCAUGAACUCCUUGAAGAACAAUCUGGCCGGGCACGGUGGCUCACGCUUGUAAUCCCAACACUUUGGGAGGCCGAGCCGGGGCGUAUCACCUGAGGUCAGGAGUUUGAGACCAGCUUGGCCAACAUGGUGAAACCCCAUCUCCACAAAAAAUACAAAAAUUAGCUAGGUGUCCUGGCGCACACCUGUAAUCCCAGCUACUCAGGAGGCUAAGGCAUGAGAAUCGCUUGAACCUGGGAGGCGGAGGUUGCAGUGAGCCAAGAUUGCACCACUGCACUCCAGCCUGGGCGACAGAGGGAGACUCCGUCUCAGAAAAAGGAAAAGAAAAACAAUCUACUUAGAUCUUAAAAUGGAUAUUUAAAAAAUUCUCCAGAGAAAGCCAGAAGAAAAUAGGUGACUUUUUCACUAUGUGCUUAGGUGACUGCAGAUGCCCGGCAAUGUUCCCUCCCAGGCCCUCCUGGGUGAGCCCGCCUCCCAGGCAGGGGUCAGCAUGGCCGGGGUCCCUCUGUCUGAGCCCAGGAUUCGUGCAACACCAGGAAGACAACAGUUGAAGGUUCCUUAGUGAGCUAAGGGAAGUAUACACAAACUUACUACAUAAACAUUAGAAAGUGCUGUCCGUAAAAAACACGUCUUCACAGAGCCAACAAGCAGAGAAAUAGCUGCCCAGUGUUAGGAAGUGCAUCAUGAUCCAGAGGUUCAGCCCGUGUGCAGCGCACAGACCUGAGGCCCCAGAGAGACCGAGGACGCAGACCAGUGGCACGACGGAAACGCAGAACGUUUAUGAGAAAACUUUCCUACUAAUUGAGAUAAAGCUGUAAAGAGGCAGAUAGCCCCACUGGGUGUGUACGUUUGAAACUUGUGCCCCCUGGGCUAGGGCAUUCGGGGUGUGGCCCUCAGUCCCCUGUAGCUGCUGCCUGGAAACCGCUGCCACCCACCCACCUCCUCCCUCUGCUCUUCCACUCAGGUGAGAAUUCUCCAAGCCCUGCCCUCCGGCGCCCCCGUCCCGCCCCUGCCCGGCCUGGCCCCGCCCCUGCCCGGCCCCGCCCCCCAACGUGUCUUCAGGUCUCUUUCCCUCCAGCCGGCCCUUAGGACGGCUGUUGGACGUGCUCGUGAGUCCUUCGCCUGUCUGCCUUCCACCUCUCUGCAGCUCCUUCUCCAAUCUCAUGGUCUUCUUGAGCUUGGCCGCCCUCCACGCCCCAUGCUGGGCUUGGUCGGUUCUGGGGUCUACCUCUCUGGCUUCAUCCCUCCCACAGUUUCGAGGGUUUCCCUGUGCUCAGGCCCCUGGCAGCCGCCCCCUGUGCAGACCACUGGGCAGAUCCAGCUGACCUCCAGGGGCACUUCCUCGGCUCAUCACUGGGCCGGUGCUCUGCAGAAUGAGCUGUGAGAGCCACUGUGGCUGGCCAGAGGGUGCCACUCACAGUCACUUCAGACUCACAGGAGCCUUCGUCCCGACCCCUGCAUUCAUCUGUGUUCUGUUUUAUGUUUUUUCCCAGUCACCUGAGCUGCAGGCCUUGGUCACCCCAGACUCCUCCCUCCUGUCACCCUUAUCCUCACCCCAGCACCUUUACGUCUGCCCCAGGCUCCAUUUCCCCCUCUUCUGCCUGGAUCAAACCACCCUGACUUUCCUGGGUCUUCGUGCAACAGCCUGCUCCGGCCGCUGCCUCACUGCACCUGCAAAUCCACUUGCACCCACACCCAGGCCAGGGUUUUUAAACAGAAGCCUCAGCAGAUCCCUCUCUCUGGCCAGCUCCCUGUUGAACCAGGAAGCAGGUCCCUGUUGAACCUCAGCAUGACCCGCCCCCACCCCUGCAUCCCACUUCUGCUCUGGGAGCCUCUGGGUUCCUGGGCGCACCUGCUGCCCUUCCCUGUUUGUCACUGGGUGACCUCCCGUCCUUGUGGGCGCUCCCGGGCCCUGGUCUCGGGCCUUCUGAGGACUUGCUCUCCUGGUAGCGGCUGCUGACUGUGAGCCCAGAGAGCAGGCGUGGCUGUUGACCUUAGGUCCUCCCAGAACCUGGCGGAUCGCCUGGCUCCCAGGCAGGAGGCGCUGCAUGACGCCUCCAACUUCCGCCAAUCUAGCCCAAGGAUGGCGUUCUAAAUAAAACGCGUUCUACAGAAAA